ACAUCAAUUGCAGCAUUGUGGCUACCAGGGGGUCAGGAUGCGGGCGGUGGAGCCCUCUGGCCUUUGUGUGGUAGCCGAGGACUCUGUGUCAGCGACCGUUUUCCGGGAAACUUCCGGGCGAGACUCACAUCUUGGAAAUUCAAAUACUCAAUAGCUCUCGAAUUCUAGGAAUCUUGAGAAGAGGCCUGGAUUAAGGAUUCAGACGUGGGCCCUCAGAUGGCCCCGCGCUCUACCCGGUUCAAGCAUGGCUGACCAGGCGCCCUUCGACACGGACGUCAACACCCUGACCCGCUUCGUCAUGGAGGAGGGCAGGAAGGCCCGCGGCACGGGCGAGUUGACCCAGCUGCUCAACUCGCUCUGCACAGCAGUCAAAGCCAUCUCUUCGGCGGUGCGCAAGGCGGGCAUCGCGCACCUCUAUGGCAUUGCUGGUUCUACCAACGUGACAGGUGAUCAAGUUAAGAAGCUGGACGUCCUCUCCAACGACCUGGUUAUGAACAUGUUAAAGUCAUCCUUUGCCACGUGUGUUCUCGUGUCAGAAGAAGAUAAACACGCCAUCAUAGUGGAACCGGAGAAAAGGGGUAAAUAUGUGGUCUGUUUUGAUCCCCUUGAUGGAUCUUCCAACAUCGAUUGCCUUGUGUCCGUUGGAACCAUUUUUGGCAUCUAUAGAAAGAAAUCAACUGAUGAGCCUUCUGAGAAGGAUGCUCUGCAACCAGGCCGGAACCUGGUGGCAGCCGGCUACGCACUGUAUGGCAGUGCCACCAUGCUGGUCCUUGCCAUGGACUGUGGGGUCAACUGCUUCAUGCUGGACCCGGCCAUCGGGGAGUUCAUUUUGGUGGACAAGGAUGUGAAGAUAAAAAAGAAAGGUAAAAUCUACAGCCUUAACGAGGGCUACGCCAGGGACUUUGACCCUGCCGUCACUGAGUACAUCCAGAGGAAGAAGUUCCCCCCAGAUAAUUCAGCUCCUUAUGGGGCCCGGUAUGUGGGCUCCAUGGUGGCUGAUGUUCAUCGCACUCUGGUCUACGGAGGGAUAUUUCUGUACCCCGCUAACAAGAAGAGCCCCAAUGGAAAGCUGAGACUGCUGUACGAAUGCAACCCCAUGGCCUACGUCAUGGAGAAGGCUGGGGGAAUGGCCACCACUGGGAAGGAGGCCGUGUUAGACGUCAUUCCCACAGACAUUCACCAGAGGGCGCCGGUGAUCUUGGGAUCCCCCGACGACGUGCUCGAGUUCCUGAAGGUGUAUGAGAAGCACUCUGCCCAGUGAGCACCUGCCCUGCCUGCAUCCGGAGAAUUGCCUCUACCUGGACCUUUUGUCUCACACAGCAGUACCCUGACCUGCUGUGCACCUUACAUUCCUAGAGAGCAGAAAUAAAAAGCAUGACUAUUUCCACCAUCAAAUGCUGUAGAAUGCUUGGCACUCCCUAACCAAAUGCUGUCUCCAUAAUGCCACUGGUGUUAAGAUAUAUUUUGAGUGGAUGGAGGAGAAAUAAACUUAUUCCUCCUUAAAAAAAA